GCGAUCGCGGAGCUGUGAGGCGCAGGCAGGGCUCUGGGGCACCUAGAGACCGGGGCCGGAGACGUGGCAGCCGCCCUGCCCGCCAGAAAGUUUCCUAGAAGUUUGCUGGGCGCGGGCGCACGACUGACUGGCUGGACCAUGAACGUGUUCCGAAUCCUCGGCGACCUGAGCCACCUCCUGGCCAUGAUCUUGCUGCUGGGGAAGAUCUGGAGGUCCAAGUGCUGCAAGGGCAUCUCUGGGAAGAGCCAGAUCCUGUUUGCUCUCGUCUUCACCACCAGGUACCUGGACCUGUUCACCAACUUCAUCUCCAUCUACAACACAGUAAUGAAGGUGGUUUUUCUCCUCUGUGCCUAUGUUACAGUGUACAUGAUAUAUGGGAAAUUCCGUAAAACUUUUGACAGUGAGAAUGACACAUUCCGCCUGGAGUUUCUUCUGGUCCCAGUCAUUGGCCUUUCCUUCCUUGAAAACUACAGUUUCACUCUGCUGGAGAUCCUCUGGACUUUCUCUAUCUAUCUGGAAUCAGUGGCUAUCCUGCCCCAGCUCUUCAUGAUCAGCAAGACUGGAGAGGCUGAGACCAUAACUACUCACUACCUGUUCUUUCUGGGUCUGUACCGGGCACUCUACCUGGCUAACUGGAUCAGGCGGUACCAGACUGAGAAUUUCUAUGACCAAAUUGCAGUCGUGUCUGGAGUAGUACAAACCAUCUUCUACUGUGACUUCUUCUACUUGUAUGUGACCAAAGUCCUUAAGGGAAAGAAGUUAAGUCUUCCAAUGCCAAUCUGAGGACCUUCAGAGACAGUCUACGCCUUAACAAGCACAUGAAGGAAACUAUUUUGAAUGUUCUCUUUGGCAACUUAUCCAUAAUUUGGGAUCAAAUGUUAAAACCAGAAAAGUGUUUAGUGUGGAUUUCAGCAAAACCUGAUCAUCCCACCCAGAAGACCUUCUCAUCAAUAGAUCGCCCUUAAAGACCCAUUGUAAGGUCAUAAAAAACCUCGGCCACCUGCACAAAGAUGGUGCCUCACUGCAACAAGAAACCUUAAGGUGUCUUACCGACGAAAUAAAAAACAUAAAUGAUUGUUCUCCAAGGCCUGAGGGCAAGACUCAUGAUGAGCAAGUCAACCCCAAUCUGGAACAAUGUCCCUCCUCUUAGAAUGUCCCAACUAAAGACCAGUUAAAAUAUUAGGGUACGUUCUUGUGAAUUUCCACUUUCCAGGUAGAUGACCAAAUUUAGGUGGUCAAGAUAUAAAGGUGUCAGCUAGUUUUAAGUGUGAAACUUAUUUCACUUUCACACUGCCUUCAGGCCAGAAGCAAACCAAAUUUACCAGGUUUGGCUGGAGGAGUUUUGUGACUCAUCUUUUACUGGUUUGAAUUUUUUCAAACCAGUGGCUGAUACCUGCCUUGUACUUAGUACCUUAAUACCAAUAACCUAAUGGUACUUAGGCGAGUACCAUUUGCACAAUCACUGUUUUACUUAUGAGCAGAUACAGAUAUAUCCAAACCCUUACCUACUAGGUAUCCUGCUAGGGUUUUCAAUUCCAAUUCUUGUAUUAAGUUUUUUCCUUUCAGUUUUAGGUGCGAAAGUAAUCAGUCAAUCCAAUAUCCCCCAUCUUUGUCUUGAAACAAAAACUGUUUUAAGACGUCUACGUUGAAUUAUUCAGAGAAUUAAGCAAUAAAAGCUCACACCUUAUUGUCAA